ACUUCCCACGCGACUUCCUGCGGGAAACAUGGCGGCAUUGAGCGGAGUCCGCUGGCUGACCCGAGCGCUGGUCUCCGCCGGGAACCCUGGGGCAUGGAGAGGUCUGAGUACCUCGGCCGCGGCGCACGCUGCAUCGCGGAGCCAGGCCGAGGACGUGAGGGUGGAGGGCUCCUUUCCCGUGACCAUGCUUCCGGGAGACGGUGUGGGGCCUGAGCUGAUGCACGCCGUCAAGGAGGUGUUCAAGGCUGCCGCUGUCCCAGUGGAGUUCCAGGAGCACCACCUGAGUGAGGUGCAGAAUAUGGCAUCUGAGGAGAAGCUGGAGCAGGUGCUGAGUUCCAUGAAGGAGAACAAAGUGGCCAUCAUUGGAAAGAUUCAUACCCCGAUGGAGUAUAAGGGGGAGCUAGCCUCCUAUGAUAUGCGGCUGAGGCGUAAGUUGGACUUAUUUGCCAACGUAGUCCAUGUGAAGUCACUUCCUGGGUAUAUGACUCGGCACAACAAUCUAGACCUGGUGAUCAUUCGAGAGCAGACAGAAGGGGAGUACAGCUCUCUGGAACAUGAGAGUGCAAGGGGUGUGAUUGAGUGUUUGAAGAUUGUCACACGAGCCAAGUCUCAGCGGAUUGCAAAGUUCGCCUUUGACUAUGCCACCAAGAAGGGGCGGGGCAAGGUCACUGCUGUCCACAAGGCCAACAUCAUGAAACUUGGGGAUGGGUUGUUCCUGCAGUGCUGUGAGGAAGUUGCUGAACUGUACCCCAAAAUCAAAUUUGAGACAAUGAUCAUAGACAACUGCUGCAUGCAGCUGGUGCAGAAUCCUUACCAGUUUGAUGUGCUUGUGAUGCCCAAUCUCUAUGGGAACAUUAUUGACAAUCUGGCUGCUGGCCUGGUUGGGGGAGCUGGUGUGGUCCCUGGUGAGAGCUAUAGUGCAGAAUACGCAGUCUUUGAGACGGGUGCCCGGCACCCAUUUGCCCAGGCAGUGGGCAGGAAUAUAGCCAAUCCCACGGCCAUGCUGCUGUCGGCUUCCAACAUGCUGCGGCAUCUUAAUCUUGAGUAUCACUCCAGCAUGAUCGCAGAUGCGGUGAAGAAGGUGAUCAAAGUUGGCAAGGUGCGGACUCGAGACAUGGGCGGCUACAGCACCACAACCGACUUCAUCAAGUCUGUCAUCGGUCACCUGCAGACUAAAGGGAGCUAGAGCCCUUUAUUUCUUCCAACCUUGCAAGGACCACACUCCCCAUACCCUUCAGUGCAGUGUACCAGGGAAGAGACCUUGUGCCUCUAAGCAGUGGACCAUGGUCACCUUGCUGGGUAGAGCCUAGGUUGUCCUUGGGCCGGCUUCCUUAGGGGACAGACUGUUGGGUGGUGAUGGGGAUUGUUAGGAUGGAGCCCAGGCCACAUGGAUGAUGAUGAUUCUCCCCCACAGGUUCGAACCUCUGACAUGGGUGGCUAUGCUACUUGCCAUGACUUCACUGAGGCUGUCAUUGCUGCCUUGCCCCACCCAUAGGCCCUGUCCAUACCCAUGUAAGGUGUUCAAUAAAGAACAUGAACCAA